AACGGCUCAGGCGGCUGCGGCUGCUACGGCGGCGCAUGCUAGGGGAUUCUGCCGGGUGAGUGCUGGGCGGCAGGACUGGGGUGGGGCGGAAGGGCUCGGCAGGAGGCCCCACGUGCAUUCCCGCGAGGGGCUCGGGGGCCGCAGUGGAAAAGAAGGGUAGGCUGCAUCUGCCUCUGCGGGGGUCCCGCCUCGGCGUCCGCCCGCUCGCCCUCUGUUACUUCUGCGGCCCCGGUGUUUCUGGAGCGUCGCUUUCCCGGUGUCUCCGCUCAGCUUUUCCCUUUCCAAAGCGCGGCCGGGGCCAGGGGAGGGCAAGGCCUGCUGUGCCCUUUGACCCCGUGCGAAAACGGCGACCCUCUGACUAUAGGGGUGUGGCCCAGAGCCACUUGGCCAGUUAGGGGUGGGGGCCGGGAUCUUUGUCCUGCGGAUCAAACAGUUGGCCCCUCUGGACUGCAUCUCCGUGCCCCCCGGCCCUGCGGGGUAGAAGAGCUGGGCCUGGAACCCAGCCCUGAGGACAUCCUGCGGCCCAGGGGCAAGUGACACCUGCUGAGAGAGGCCCAGGAUGGUGGAGGCUGAGGAACUGGCACAGCUGCGGCUGCUCAAUCUGGAGCUCCUGAGGCAGCUGUGGGUGGGGCAGGAUGCUGUGCGGCGGUCAGUGGCCAGGGCAGCCUCGGAGUCAAGCCUGGAAUCCAGCAGCAGCUACAACUCAGAGACUCCAUCGACCCCAGAGACGUCCUCAACUUCCUUGAGCACCUCCUGCCCACGGGGCCGGUCCUCCGUGUGGGGCCCACCAGAUGCCUGUCGAGGGGACCUCCGUGAUGUGGCCAGAUCGGGGGUGGCCUCUCUCCCACCUGCCAAAUGCCAGCACCAGGAGUCCCUGGGCCGACCGAGACCCCACUCAGCACCCUCGCUGGGCACCUCAAGCCUGAGGGACCCAGAGCCCUCAGGGAGGCUGGGUGAUCCAGGACCCCAGGAGGCACAGACCCCGAGGUCCAUCCUGGCUCAACAGAGCAAGCUGUCCAAGCCCAGGGUGACCUUCUCUGAGGAGUCUGCAGUUCCUAAGAGGAGCUGGCGCCUCAGGCCAUACCUGGGCUAUGACUGGAUUGCAGGGUCUCUGGACACCAGCUCUUCCAUCACCAGCCAGCCUGAGGCCUUCUUCUCCAAGCUGCAGGAGUUUCGGGAAACCAACAAGGAGGAGUGUAUCUGCAGCCAUCCUGAACCCCAGUUGCCAGGCCUGCGUGAGAGCAGUGGCAGCGGCGUGGAGGAAGACCAUGAAUGCGUGUACUGUUACCGUGUCAACCGGCGCCUGUUCCCGGUGCCUGUGGAUCCCGGUACCCCCUGCCGCCUGUGCAGGACACCGCGAGACCAGCAGGGCCCUGGGACCCUGGCGCAGCCAGCGCACGUCAGGGUGAGCAUCCCGCUGUCGAUCCUGGAGCCCCCGCACCGGUACCACAUCCACCGGCGAAAGAGCUUUGACGCCUCUGACACACUGGCCCUGCCCCGGCACUGCCUGCUGGGCUGGGACAUUUUUCCUCCGAAGUCUGAGAAAAGCUCAGCCCCCAGGAACCUGGACCUCUGGUCCUCUGUCUCCGCUGAGGCCCAGCACCAGAAGCUGUCCGGCACCAGCAGCCCUUUUCACCCGGCCUCACCAAUGCAGAUGCUGCCCCCGACCCCGACCUGGUCAGUGCCCCAGGUCCCUCGGCCCCACGUCCCACGGCAGAAGCCCUGAGGACUGACUCCUGGGGGAGAACAGCAUUCCCGCCGCCUCCAGCCUCUCCCCUCUGGCAGGCGCACCCAGGAGAUGGAAUCCCCUGCCCGCCCAGCUCAGGCCCAGCUGUCCUAGGUUGGGCAGGUGGGUGGACCCAAGCUUGUCUGCUGCCUGAGUUCCAGAGAGGGAGGACCCUGGGGUGGAGGGUGAGGGAUUCUGUGGAAGUUUGUAAAUAAAGCUCAGUGCUCUGCAGCUCAA